AUCGCCGGGGAGAGCCUUCCGGACUCCGGGCGGCGGCUGGCUGGGGGCGCGUUCCGAGGCGCCCUCAGGCAGGGCGCGGGGGCAGAGCCUCGCCUGGGUUCUGGAGGCUGCGGGGCCAUCGCUCCAGAUGCGAAAGCCAUGGAGUUGAGCUGCAGCGAAGCACCUCUUUACGGGCAGAUGAUGAUCUAUGCGAAGUUUGACAAAAAUGUGUAUCUUCCUGAAGAUGCUGAGUUUUACUUUACUUAUGACGGAUCUCAUCAGCGACAUGUCAUGAUUGCAGAGCGCAUCGAGGAUAACGUUCUCCAGUCCAGCGUCCCAGGCCAUGGGCUUCAGGAGACGGUGACGGUAUCUGUGUGCCUCUGCUCGGAAGGUUACUCUCCGGUGACCAUGGGCUCUGGCUCAGUGACCUACGUGGACAACAUGGCUUGCAGGCUGGCUCGUCUGCUGGUGACGCAGGCCAAUCGCCUCACAGCCUGCAGCCACCAGACCCUGCUGACCCCAUUUGCCUUGACGGCAGGAGCACUGCCUGCCUUGGAUGAGGAGCUCGUGCUGGCUCUGACCCAUCUGGAAUUGCCUCUAGAGUGGACUGUGUUGGGAAGUUCUUCACUUGAAGUAUCUUCUCACAGAGAAUCUCUUCUACACCUGGCUAUGAGAUGGGGCCUGGCUAAACUUUCCCAGUUCUUCUUGUGUCUCCCGGGGGGAGUCCAGGCCUUGGCUUUACCCAACGAAGAGGGUGCCACACCAUUAGACUUAGCUUUACGUGAAGGACACUCCAAGCUGGUGGAAGACGUCACAAAUUUUCAGGGCAGAUGGUCCCCAAGCUUCUCCCGAGUGCAGCUCAGUGAAGAAGCCUCCUUGCAUUACAUUCACUCAUCGGAAACGCUGACCCUGACCCUGAACCACACAGCCGAGCAUUUGUUGGAGGCAGAUAUUAAACUCUUCCGGAAAUACUUUUGGGAUAGAGCCUUUCUUGUCAAGGCCUUUGAGCCAGAAGCCAGGCCAGAGGAAAGAACAGCUAUGCCCUCCAGCGGUGCAGAAACUGAAGAAGAGAUUAAGAAUUCAGUGUCCAGCAGAUCAGCAGCUGAAAAGGAAGAUAUAAAGCGUGUCAAAAGCCUGGUGGUUCAACACAAUGAACAUGAAGACCAGCACAGCCUAGAUUUGGAUCGCUCCUUCGAUAUCCUAAAAAAAUCCAAGCCGCCCUCGACAUUGCUUGCUGCAGGCCGGCUUUCAGACAUGCUGAAUGGAGGUGAUGAAGUCUACGCUAACUGUAUGGUGAUUGAUCAGGUUGGUGAUUUGGAUAUCAGCUAUAUUAAUAUAGAGGGAAUCACUGCCACUACCAGCCCUGAAUCCAGAGGUUGCACUCUGUGGCCUCAGAGCAGCAAACACACCCUUCCUACAGAAACCAGUCCCAGUGUGUACCCACUUAGUGAAAAUGUCGAAGGGACAGCACACACUGAAGCCCAGCAGUCCUUCAUGUCACCAUCAAGUUCGUGUGCUUCCAACUUGAAUCUUUCUUUUGGUUGGCAUGGAUUUGAAAAGGAACAAAGUCAUCUAAAGAAAAGAAGUUCUAGCCUUGAUGCCUUGGACGCCGACAGUGAAGGGGAAGGGCAUUCUGAGCCAUCCCACAUCUGUUACACUCCAGGGUCUCAGAGCUCCUCAAGAACUGGGAUUCCUAGUGGGGAUGAAUUGGACUCUUUUGAGACUAACACUGAACCGGAUUUUAAUAUCUCCAGGGCUGAAUCCCUUCCUCUAUCAAGUAAUCUACAGUCGAAGGAAUCACUGCUUUCUGGAGUUCGCUCACGUUCUUAUUCUUGCUCAUCACCCAAAAUUUCUUUAGGAAAAACUCGUUUGGUGCGUGAAUUAACAGUAUGCAGUUCAAGUGAAGAGCAAAGAGCUUACAGCUUAUCGGAGCCACCAAGAGAAAACAGAAUUCAGGAAGAAGAAUGGGAUAAAUACAUCAUACCUGCCAAAUCAGAGUCUGAAAAAUAUAAAGUGAGUCGAACUUUCAGUUUCCUCAUGAAUAGGAUGACUAGCCCUCGGAAUAAAUCAAAGACAAAAAGCAAGGAUGCCAAAGAUAAAGAGAAGCUGAAUCGACAUCAGUUUGCCCCAGGAACAUUCUCUGGGGUUCUGCAGUGUUUGGUUUGUGAUAAAACACUCCUGGGGAAAGAGUCACUGCAGUGUUCUAACUGUAAUGCAAAUGUGCACAAAGGUUGUAAAGAUGCUGCGCCUGCAUGCACCAAGAAAUUCCAAGAGAAAUAUAACAAGAACAAACCACAGACCAUCCUUGGAAAUUCUUCAUUUAGAGACAUCCCACAGCCUGGUCUCUCCUUGCACCCUUCUUCCUCCGUGCCUGUUGGAUUGCCGACUGGAAGGAGGGAGACUGUGGGACAGGUCCAUCCAUUGUCCAGAAGUGUUCCAGGCACCACCUUGGAAAGCUUCAGGAGGUCAGCCACAUCCUUGGAGUCUGAGAGUGACCAUAACAGCUGCAGAAGCAGGUCUCAUUCUGAUGAGCUGCUACAGUCCAUGGGCUCUUCUCCCUCUACAGAGUCUUUCAUAAUGGAAGAUGUUGUGGAUUCUUCUCUGUGGAGUGACCUCAGCAGUGAUGCCCAGGAGUUUGAAGCAGAAUCUUGGAGUCUUGUGGUGGAUCCCUCAUUUUGUAAUAGGCAGGAGAAGGAUGUCAUCAAAAGACAGGAUGUCAUUUUUGAGCUAAUGCAAACAGAGAUGCAUCACAUCCAGACCCUGUUCAUCAUGUCUGAGAUCUUCAGGAAAGGCAUGAAAGAGGAGCUGCAGCUGGACCACAGCACCGUGGAUAAAAUUUUCCCCUGUUUAGAUGAGUUGCUUGAAAUCCACAGGCAUUUCUUCUACAGUAUGAAGGAACGAAGGCAGGAAUCCUGUGCUGGCAGCGACAGGAAUUUUGUGAUCGACCGAAUUGGAGAUAUUUUGGUACAACAGUUUUCAGAAGAAAAUGCAAGUAAAAUGAAGAAAAUAUAUGGAGAAUUCUGUUGCCAUCAUAAAGAAGCUGUUAACCUCUUUAAAGAACUCCAGCAGAAUAAAAAGUUUCAGAAUUUUAUUAAGCUCCGAAAUAGUAAUCUUUUGGCUCGACGCCGAGGAAUUCCAGAAUGCAUUCUGUUGGUCACUCAGCGUAUUACAAAAUACCCUGUCUUGGUGGAAAGGAUAUUGCAGUACACAAAGGAAAGAACUGAGGAACAUAAAGACUUACGCAAAGCGCUUUGCUUAAUUAAAGACAUGAUUGCAACAGUGGAUUUAAAAGUCAAUGAAUAUGAGAAAAACCAAAAAUGGCUUGAGAUCCUAAAUAAGAUUGAAAACAAAACAUACACGAAGCUCAAAAAUGGACAUGUGUUUAGGAAGCAGGCACUGAUGAGUGAAGAAAGGACUCUGUUAUAUGAUGGCCUUGUUUACUGGAAAACUGCUACAGGUCGUUUCAAAGAUAUCCUAGCUCUACUUCUAACUGAUGUGCUGCUCUUUUUACAAGAAAAAGACCAGAAAUACAUCUUUGCAGCCGUUGAUCAGAAGCCAUCAGUUAUUUCCCUUCAAAAGCUUAUUGCUAGAGAAGUUGCUAAUGAGGAGAGAGGAAUGUUUCUGAUCAGUGCUUCAUCUGCUGGUCCUGAGAUGUAUGAAAUUCACACCAAUUCCAAGGAGGAACGCAAUAACUGGAUGAGACGGAUCCAGCAGGCUGUAGAAAGUUGUCCUGAAGAAAAAGGGGGAAGGACAAGUGAAUCUGAUGAAGACAAGAGGAAAGCUGAAGCCAGAGUGGCCAAAAUUCAGCAAUGUCAAGAAAUACUCACUAACCAAGACCAACAAAUUUGUGCGUAUUUGGAGGAGAAGCUGCAUAUCUAUGCUGAACUUGGAGAACUGAGCGGAUUUGAGGACGUCCAUCUAGAGCCCCACCUCCUUAUUAAACCUGACCCAGGCGAGCCUCCCCAGGCAGCCUCAUUACUGGCAGCAGCACUGAAAGAAGCUGAGAGCCUACAAGUUGCAGUGAAGGCCUCACAGAUGGGCGCCGUGAGUCAAUCAUGUGAGGACAGUUGUGGAGACUCUGUCUUGGCGGACACACUCAGUUCUCAUGAUGUACCAGGAUCACCGACUGCCUCAUUAGUCACAGGAGGGAGAGAAGGAAGAGGCUGUUCGGAUGUGGAUCCCGGGAUCCAGGGUGUGGUAACCGACUUGGCCGUCUCUGAUGCAGGGGAGAAGGUGGAAUGUAGAAAUUUUCCAGGUUCUUCACAAUCAGAGAUUAUACAAGCCAUACAGAAUUUAACCCGUCUCUUAUACAGCCUUCAGGCCGCCUUGACCAUUCAGGACAGCCACAUUGAGAUCCACAGGCUGGUUCUCCAGCAGCAGGAGGGCCUGUCUCUCGGCCACUCUAUCCUCCGAGGCGGCCCCUUGCAGGACCAGAAGUCUCGCGACGCGGACAGGCAGCAUGAGGAGCUGGCCAAUGUGCACCAGCUUCAGCACCAGCUCCAGCAGGAGCAGCGGCGCUGGCUGCGCAGGUGUGAGCAGCAGCAGCGGGCGCAGGCGACCAGGGAGAGCUGGCUGCAGGAGCGGGAGCGGGAGUGCCAGUCGCAGGAGGAGCUGCUGCUGCGGAGCCGGGGCGAGCUGGACCUCCAGCUCCAGGAGUACCAGCACAGCCUGGAGCGGCUGAGGGAGGGCCAGCGCCUGGUGGAGAGGGAGCAGGCGAGGAUGCGGGCCCAGCAGAGCCUGCUGGGCCACUGGAAGCACGGCCGGCAGAGGAGCCUGCCCGCGGUGCUCCUUCCGGGUGGCCCCGAGGUAAUGGAACUUAAUCGAUCUGAGAGUUUAUGUCAUGAAAACUCAUUCUUCAUCAAUGAAGCUUUAGUACAAAUGUCAUUUAACACUUUCAACAAACUGAAUCCAUCAGUUAUCCAUCAGGAUGCCACUUACCCUACAACUCAAUCUCAUUCUGACUUGGUGAGGACUAGUGAACAUCAAGUAGACCUCAAGGUGGACCCUUCUCAGCCUUCGAAUGUCAGUCACAAACUGUGGACAGCCGCUGGUUCCGGCCAUCAGAUACUUCCUUUCCAUGAAAGCAGCAAGGAUUCUUGUAAAAAUGGCUCCAGUAUGACAAAGUGCAGUUGUACGUUGACAUCUCCCCCGGGACUGUGGACUGGAACCACAUCUACUUUGAAAGAUUUGGACACCUCCCACACUGAGUCCCCAACCCCCCAUGACUCAAAUUCACACCGCCCUCAACUGCAGGCGUUUAUAACAGAAGCAAAGCUAAAUCUACCGACAAGGACAAUGACCAGACAAGAUGGGGAAACUGGAGAUGGAGCCAAAGAAAAUAUUGUUUACCUCUAAUUGUGUUGUCAUUUUUCCAAACAAAACAAAACACUGGCACUUUUGGGAGAAACUUUUUGUCUCCAUUCCUUAUGUAUGUGUGAUUGUCUGUGUCCAAAUUGCUUUAAGAAUAAUAUUUAAUAUUUCCUGGAAGCUCAUUUUUUUGGCAUGAGUCUAAUUAAAUUAUUGAAAGCCACCCUGUUUGUAUAAUCUUUAACUUAUCAAAUCUAAUUUCAGAUUUCUGGAGGAGAAACUAACUUGAAUAAGCAGGACUAUUUUAAAAGUUGUUUUGACGCUAGAGUAAAAUUCCAUGUCACAUUUUCUACCCAAUCAUCUGGAUUUCAAGAUUCCUUUUAAGAUCUCAAUGAAGCAAUUUGGAUUUAAAGAGUGGUAUUCACAAGGGGUGAACUUUCACAGUCAGGGCAGUUGCCUCAGUGCCCACAUAGGCAGAGGAGGAUGUGGGAAAGGGUUUUUCUCAGCUAGUUUUUGUGUGCUCAUUUCUUCUGGGAGCAUUAAAAGUGGUGAUCUGUUACAGUCACUAUUCAACUGGGCACGUGUUGUGAUUGGUCAGUCACUGAGCCAGGGAUACAGUCCGGACUUGCUUAGUACCUAAGCCUAAUGCUGGUGGGGUUUCAAGACAUGGUUCAGCAUCAUCUUUUAACAAGGCCCAGAGGCCCAGAGCCCCCAUCAAGUCAUUUUGAUGUAAAUAGUGAACUUUGUUAGAGCCCUCACUUCUAUCAAUCAGCUGUCCUGUCCCUGCCAGCACCUGGAGCACCAACUACCACUCCCUGGAAAGAACCCUUCCCUGCAGUUUUUUAAGGACAAAACUGCCCACUCCUCAUUAAGUUUGCUGCCUGGAUACACUUUUCCACAAAGGAAAACUGGCAUAUCCUGCCUUCCGAGUAGUAUGGGUCUCUGUGUGAGAAACCAGGAGAUAUUUUCAUCUUGUUCGGAAAUACUUGUAUGUAUUUUGGUGUCAAUAAAUAUCUUGUACCUCA